AGUCGCGUCAAGCAGGCUAUUCCGGGUUUGUGGCUGCUUGGCUCCACACGUGGGCCGCCGUAGGUAUUCCGACCGGUAAUUCCUCCUAUUGGUGUGCAGCAGCCACAUUGAAGGAUAGAGUGGCAGCAGAGGCCAAGGAUCGUGAGUUGAUGGAGUUUGCUGCUGAAAAUGAAGGGAAGUCUGGGGGAGGUCUCCACAGCGUAGCUGAGGGGGUGCGGCUAAGUCCAGAGCCUGGCAGGGAGGGAGUAAGGGACUUAGCAGGGGCGGAGGAGUUCGGCGGCGGAGAGGAGGGGACAGGGCUGACAGGGAUAAAGGAGAUAGGGGAUGGAGAGGAAGGAAGUGGACAAAGGCCAGAGGAAAUACCGAUGGACCUAACGGUAGUGAAGCAGGAAAUUAUAGACUGGCCAGGUACAGAAGGCAGGUUGGCUGGCCAGUGGGUAGAACAGGAGGUGGAGGAUAGGCCUGAGGUGAAGGAUGAGAACGCAGGCGUAUUGGAGGUGAAGCAGGAGACGGAUAGUAGUUUAGUGGUAAAAGAAGCGAAGGUGGGUGAACCAGAGGUAAAGGAAGAGAAGGUAAAGGAAGAGGUAAUGGACUGGUCAGAAGUGAAGGAAGAGAAGGAUAACUUGGAGAUAAAACAGGAGGAGAAGUUUGUUGGUCAAUGCAUAAAAGAGGAAUUGAUGCAUGGAGAGUGUGUAAAAGAAGAGAAGGAUUUCCUGAAGAAAGAAAUCGUGGAUGAUACAAAGGUGAAAGAAGAGCCUCCGAUAAAUCACCCGGUGGGCUGCAAGCGGAAACUGGCCAUGUCAAGGUGUGAGACUUGUGGUACAGAAGAAGCAAAGUACAGAUGUCCACGUUGUAUGCGAUAUUCCUGCAGUUUGCCCUGUGUAAAGAAACACAAAGCAGAACUGACAUGUAAUGGAGUUCGAGAUAAAACUGCAUACAUUUCAAUACAACAGUUUACUGAAAUGAAUCUCCUAAGUGAUUAUCGAUUUUUGGAAGAUGUGGCAAGAACAGCGGACCAUAUUUCUAGAGAUGCUUUUUUGAAGAGACCAAUAAGCAAUAAAUAUAUGUACUUUAUGAAAAAUCGUGCCCGGAGGCAAGGUAUUAACUUAAAACUUCUACCCAAUGGAUUCACCAAGAGGAAGGAGAAUUCAACCUUUUUUGAUAAGAAAAAACAACAGUUUUGUUGGCAUGUGAAGCUCCAGUUUCCUCAAAGUCAAGCUGAGUACAUAGAAAAAAGAGUACCAGAUGAUAAAACUAUUAAUGAAAUCCUAAAACCUUACAUUGAUCCUGAAAAGUCUGAUCCUGUAAUUCGUCAAAGGUUGAAAGCCUACAUUCGCUCUCAGACUGGGGUUCAGAUUUUAAUGAAGAUUGAAUAUAUGCAGCAAAAUUUAGUAAGAUAUUAUGAACUAGAUCCUUAUAAAAGUCUCCUAGACAAUUUGAGGAACAAAGUGAUCAUUGAGUAUCCAACAUUACAUGUGGUAUUGAAAGGAUCCAAUAAUGACAUGAAAGUUCUUCACCAAGUGAAGAGUGAAUCUACCAAGAACGUUGGCAAUGAAAAUUGAGCAUUUUUUCUGGAAGAAGAAAGUGAAAACUUCCAGACAACUGCAGCAGACUCUGCAUUGAUGGGCUGUUGGCUGAUUGGGGUAUUGUCAAUGGGUGAUUGGAAUUUUUUCUUUGUAUGAAAAAUAAGCUUAACUCUUUUAAAAAAUGUAUUUUAUAACCUCUUGAAUUAAUUGACUUGUAAGACCCAUUUAUUCAUAUUAAGAACUCUCCUUUGCACUUGAUCAGCAUAGUACUUAUUAGGCCCUGGCUUUUUAAUAUGCUUAAUUGCUUAAUUCCAUAAACUGAAAACUUUUUUUUUCUUUUUUCUUUCUUUUUUUGAGAUGGGGUCUUGGAGUGCAAGUGGUAUGAGCAUAGCUUCCUCAAAUUCCUGGGCUCGAAUGGUCCUCUCACUGCAGCCUCCCAACAGGCUGGUACCACCACACUCAGCUAAGUUUUUUGUUGUUGUUUUUUUUUGGUAGAGACAGGGUUGCGCUCUUUCGCCCAGGCUGGUCUCAAAUUUGUGGCCUCAAGCAAUCCUUCCACCUCAGACUCCAAAGCAUUGGGAUUACAGGCAUCAGCCACCACACCUGGCCUUGAACAUUUUUUAUUUGUUAAUUUCAUGCGUGACGAAACCCAAGGAUCACCCAUGUCAACCACAAAGUUGGCAUUCCCUUUAGUAGAACCUCACUAAACGGAAAGGCUGUACAACGCACCGUCUAGCCACAGGAGAACUAAUCUUCUAUCAGUUGCCCUUUCUUCUUUGGAGUUUUUAUGUAACUUACCCUUGUGAGACAAGUUUUCUACUUGAGAAACUCCUAGUACAAUGUCUUAUACUAGAAGCCUGGAUAAAUACUAUUAACUACUGUUUCUUAUAUUCACUUCAGAAAAUCAGUGGCUCCACAUUGUUUGAGCCAUUAGUGAUAACAAAUUUGGAUCUACUUACUCAAGUCUUAUGAAUUCUGUGCCUUUCAUCACAUUCCUAGCCCACUCUCAUCAUUACUGCAGAAGGGUGUUGUGAUGACCAGUUUUAUACUGUGUUUUGAUAUGUCUAGCAAUAACUUAAAGAAAAAAAAACCUGGGAAAUCUUCAACAUGUUAUUGGAACAUAUAUGUAUGUAUUAAUGUAUAUACAUGGCUUAACUUAUACGUUAUGGCAGCUCUGUAUACAGUUUGAUCUCAUGUACUGAAAAAAAAUUCUUAAUUUUAUUGGAGUUUAUACCACUGUGAAACUGCAAUAUGACUGUAAGAGAGUAAAAAGAUUGUUACAUCUAUAUUGUAUGUGUGUACUUAAUGGUUAAAAAGCAAUGAUAAAACUGGACAUUAAUGAAAUUGAUUUUUAGUUACAGUUGGAAUAAGUUUUUUACCAAAAAGAAACCAGAGACGUUAGUUAAGGAGACUUAAAAAGAUCUGAAAUAUGAAAAGAGAAUGAGAAGAUGAGCAGAAGAUAAAUUUGUGGGACACAAGUAUAACUUGGGGUAGAAACUGGAGAAGAGAAUCGAAAAACAAUAAUGCCAGAAGGACCCUUGGUAUGAAAGUACUAAUGGAAUGUGAUUCAUAGAAAGUUCAUAGAAAGUGAGUCCUUGCAACUUGAGAAACAUACAUACAUAUAUAUUUAUAAUCUCUAAAGCAACAUCAGGAAUCUUCUAAUAUAUGAUAAAGAAUUUGUGUAGAAUUACGUUGUUCACAGUAUUAUUGGAGAGACAAAUAAGAUUUCAAGGAAUUCAUUUAUAAUCAAAAGUGAAAUGUGUCUUCUUGAAACCAGCAAGAAAUAGAUGAAUUGAGUGAAACGUGUUGUUAUUAGGAGAAGUGGGAUAACGUAUACAAAAAGAACUUGCGAUCUGAAUAUGAUCUGAAUAUGAGGGUGGAUAGGAAUUUUUUGACAGUGAAAUCUGUUAUGAUGUAGUCUCAUUUCCAAGAAAAGUCUUGAGUUCCAUCCCCCCUUCUGAAUUUAAAUUGAAACCUGGACAGAAAACAAACUAUCCUGUAGUUUCCACUGCUCAGGAGGAAAAAAAGAAAUCUAUAUUAUCUAAUGCAUCUUUGCCAUCUUUAUUUUCUAGAAUUCUAUUAGACUUUUCAAUUAUAGGCUAUUAGGAAAGAAUAUAACUCUUAGAAUUCCCCUAAAUAUAAUUAUCAACUCAUUUGAUUAAUAUGCAUAUUUUUUCCCGUAAGAUUUACAAUACACGUGUGUUUUAGUGAAUUACCAAUGGCUUGGAGAGAAUGAAAUUGGAAUAACUAACUGAAAACCCUAGAUGUUUGUAGCAUUGAGACCCAAUAUCUUUUUGGAGGCCCUCUCCAUGUUAGCUUAUUGUCAAAUUCUGGUGUGUAAACAAACUCCUUGACCCAUGUUAAGUUCAGCAUCCUGCAUUUUGUUCAUGAAUCACAUUUUAAAAGGAGAAAAGCUCCACCUGGUUUUCUUUAUUUUUUUAAACAGUGAUUUCAAAGAGAAGAUAGGCCUUUCAUAAUUGCUAAUUAUACAUAUAGGAUUAAUAGUCAUAAAUUAUAGUAAAUAAAACUUGUACCUAUUCCUUUUAUAAAUAUGAAUUGGCUAGGCACAGUGGCUCACAGCUGUAAUCCCAGCACUUUGGGAGGCUGAGGCGGGCAGAUCACAAGGUCAGGUGUUUGAGACUAGCCUGGCCAACAUGGCAAAACCCUGUGUCUACUAAAAAUACAAAAAUUAGCCAGGCGUGGUGGCAGGCACCUGUAAUUCCAGCUACUCAGGAAGCUGGGGCACGAGAAUCACUUGAACCCUGGUGGCAGAGUUUGCAGUGAGCUGAGAUUGUUCCACUGCAUUCCUGGGCACUGCCUGGGUGACAGAAUGAGACUCUGCCUCAAAAAAAAAAAAAGUUAUUAAAAAUAGAUAUUUAAGAUUCCAAAAUGUAGUUGAUCCAGUUUGUUUCCCUGUAGCAAGUAGUGGGAUUUGGGUUUCAUGACAUAUAAUUAAAAUGUUAAUCACAUAACUAUAAUGCCAACAAUUUUCUUUAUACAUUUUUGUUUAAUUAUGUUGACAUAUACUUUGUGUUGUACCUUAUUUCAUGUUACUAAAUUUUACAUAAAGAUGCUGGUCUAUUUUUAUUUAAUCAUAUACUGUUAUGGUUUGAAUAUAGUUUGUUCCUACCAAAACUCAUGUUGAAAUUAGAUUCCCCAUGUGCUAGUGUUGGGAGGCAGAGCCUAAUGGAAGGUGUUUGGGUCAUGGGGGCAGAUAGAUCCCACAUGAAUAAACUAAUGCCCUCCUACUGGGGUGAGUGAGUUCUCAUUCUUGCUGUCGUGGGAAUGGAUUAGUUCUCACAAGCAAGGGUUACUAAAGAGUCUGGCUUUCUUGAUUUUCUCCUUUUUGCCUCCUGCCUUCCCAUGUGAUCUCUUUGCACAUACCUACUCCCCUUUCACUUUGUACCAAGAGUGGAAGCAACAUGAGACCCUCACCAGAUACAGCUGCCCAAUCUUGAGCCUUCCAGCCACCAGAAUCAUGAGCCAAAUAAAACUCUUUUUAAAAAUAAGUUACCCAGUCUUAGAUAUUCUAUUAUAGCGACACAAAAUGGACUAAGCUGUACUCUGUUGCAUUAAAAUGUGUUGUUUAUAUGCAAGUGACAAAAACUCAAAAUAGUGUCAGCAUGAAGGGCAGUUCAUUGGCUUAUAUACAGGGAAGUCCAGGCAAUGACUGGGUCCUGGGUCCAAACGUCAAAAGCAGUCAUCUUGCCAUCCUACACACUUGGCUCUGAUUAUUUUCUUCUUUAUGGAUUGGUUUUCUUUUCAGAUUUUCCCUUUGGGGAUAUUCUGUAUGGGAUGAGGAACAGUGAGGUGAGAGGAUGGUGGAUAACAGCAAUUGACAUUUUCAGCUUACCUUAGCAUAACAAGGCUGAAAGCUUUUAUAAAGCAAGCUAUGUAAAAUUUUGGAGAAGUACUUUUAUUUUGCCCAGAUUGGAUCACAUUCCGUUCCUGAGCUAAUCAAGAGAGGAAUUCACCCAAAGGAGGGGGAAAUUUUUAGAAGAAAGCCAGAAUGUAGGGAGCAGGUGAGGAAAGGUAGUUACUGGGAAUACGAAAGUAACACAUUCAUUGCACCCUGUUUGAAUUUGAGUAGCAAGAAGUUUCUGAUUUGUACUAACAGAAGGAGUAAAGUUCAGAUUUAAUCUGCAAGUCUUGAUUGUUUUUAACUAGAGAUUUUAAUCUCUUCUUCUUAUUAUUGCUGCUUUGAGUUGCCAUUAUAGGUUUUUGGAUUUUUUUUUUAAUGCCAUCCAUUUUUAUUUGACAUCAUGUUGUUGCUAGUUUGAGCAGAUGCACAUAGCAUAUGUUUCCAUUACCAAUUUGGAAAUUUUUCCCAGUGGCAUCAGCAUUUGAGAGAUACUGAUUUUGAAAUUAGAGUACUAGGGGAAAAUGCUUCAAAAAUGAAGACUACUUAAAUAAAAAUUGGCUUUAAAUAAACCUUUGGGGAUCUGUACUUGACUAAAAAGUAUUUUCUUUAAACUUUGGUCUUUGAAAACUAAAGUGUGUGUGCAUGUGUUCAUUAAAAUGACCUAUAACAUGAACAUUUUCCAUACUGGAGUGUGAUGUACUGUACUCAUUUUGAACUUUAGAACCAAAUGCAUCCUUUAGCAUUUGAUGAGCUGCUAUAUAAUUCUAUUUCCAGUUUUAUUUUCUUGCCAAAUAAAGUACCAAAGCUCAGCCUGA